ACAUCCAGAGCUGGCCGACGGGUGCGCGGGCGGGCGGCGGCACCAUGCAGGGAAGCUGCCAGGGGCCGUGGGCAGCGCCGCUUUCUGCCGCCCACCUGGCGCUGUGAGACUGGCGCUGCCACCAUGUUCCCCAGCCCUGCUCUCACGCCCACGCCCUUCUCAGUCAAAGACAUCCUAAACCUGGAACAGCAGCAGCGCAGCCUGGCUGCCGCCGGAGAGCUCUCUGCCCGCCUGGAGGCGACCCUGGCGCCCUCCUCCUGCAUGCUGGCCGCCUUCAAGCCAGAGGCCUACGCUGGGCCCGAGGCGGCUGCGCCGGGCCUCCCAGAGCUGCGCGCAGAGCUGGGCCGCGCGCCUUCACCGGCCAAGUGUGCGUCUGCCUUUCCCGCCGCCCCCGCCUUCUAUCCACGUGCCUACAGCGACCCCGACCCAGCCAAGGACCCUAGAGCCGAAAAGAAAGCCUGAAAUUUUAAGUCACCGUCUGUCUCCCUCACCAGGGUGUGAACUGCCCCGAGGGCAGAGACCUCCCGUUUUGUUCUCCAGCGCCUUGAGCCAGCCUGACUUUCUACAAAUGCUGAGUGAGACGUGUCGGUGGCUCCCAGUGCACUUGGCAGAGUGAGCCGCAGCCAGCUGGGCGCUCCAGGCAGGACACAGUGGCCUCCACGAGGAUCCCUUACCAUUACUGUGCGGCCGCGCUCCGUAGGUCAAGCCGCUCUUACCAAGCGUCUCUCUGCCUCUCUGUUCCCCCUCAGAGCUGUGCGCGCUGCAGAAGGCGGUGGAGCUGGAGAAGACAGAGGCGGACAACGCGGAGCGGCCCCGGGCGCGACGGCGGAGGAAGCCGCGCGUGCUCUUCUCGCAGGCGCAGGUCUAUGAGCUGGAGCGGCGCUUCAAGCAGCAGCGGUACCUGUCGGCCCCCGAACGCGACCAGCUGGCCAGCGUGCUGAAACUCACGUCCACGCAGGUCAAGAUCUGGUUCCAGAACCGGCGCUACAAGUGCAAGCGGCAGCGGCAGGACCAGACUCUGGAGCUGGUGGGGCUGCCCCCGCCGCCGCCGCCGCCUGCCCGCAGGAUCGCGGUGCCAGUGCUGGUGCGCGAUGGCAAGCCAUGCCUAGGGGACUCGGCGCCCUACGCGCCUGCCUACGGCGUGGGCCUCAAUCCCUACGGUUAUAACGCCUACCCCGCCUAUCCGGGUUACGGCGGCGCGGCCUGCAGCCCUGGCUACAGCUGCACUGCCGCUUACCCCGCCGGGCCUUCCCCAGCGCAGCCGGCCACUGCCGCCGCCAACAACAACUUCGUGAACUUCGGCGUCGGGGACUUGAAUGCGGUUCAGAGCCCCGGGAUUCCGCAGAGCAACUCGGGAGUGUCCACGCUGCAUGGUAUCCGAGCCUGGUAGGGAAGGGACCCGCGUGGCGCGACCCUGACCGAUCCCACCUCAACAGCUCCCUGACUCUCGGGGGGAGAAGGGGCUCCCAACAUGACCCUGAGUCCCCUGGAUUUUGCAUUCACUCCUGCGGAGACCUAGGAACUUUUUCUGUCCCACGCGCGUUUGUUCUUGCGCACGGGAGAGUUUGUGGCGGCGAUUAUGCAGCGUGCAAUGAGUGAUCCUGCAGCCUGGUGUCUUAGCUGUCCCCCCAGGAGUGCCCUCCGAGAGUCCAUGGGCACCCCCGGUUGGAACUGGGACUGAGCUCGGGCACGCAGGGCCUGAGAUCUGGCCGCCCAUUCCGCGAGCCAGGGCCGGGCGCCCGGGCCUUUGCUAUCUCGCCGUCGCCCGCCCACGCACCCACCCGUAUUUAUGUUUUUACCUAUUGCUGUAAGAAAUGACGAUCCCCUUCCCAUUAAAGAGAGUGCGUUGA